ACUCGGCUCACGUGACGUUUCGCCGGCCGGGGGCGGACUGGGAAGCCGGCAGAAAUGGAACGAUUUUUACCGCGGUGCGACGUGUCGGCUUUGCACUUGGCGGUGGUUCAGGAGCCAGUUCUGCAGAGCUGGGUGGGGAAGGGCUGGGGGCGAGAGGAGAGGCUGCCCCGAGGAACGUGGUGGCCUCAGGGCAGUGGACUCUGCAGCGCCGGAGGCCCUCAUCUGCCUUUAGAAUGUGAGAUCCCCGAGGGCAGAUCCUGUGCUACACACCUUUUGUAUUUUUGGUGCCUGGCAGGAUACCAUGAAGAGGACCUACGCAUAGCAGCAAUGAAUGUGGAUCACGAGGUUAACCUCUUAGUGGAGGAAAUUCAUCGUUUGGGUUCAAAAAAUGCUGAUGGAAAGUUAAGCGUGAAAUUUGGGGUCCUCUUCCGUGAUGAUAAAUGUGCCAACCUCUUUGAAGCAUUGGUAGGAACUCUUAAAGCUGCAAAACGAAGGAAGAUUGUAACAUAUCCAGGAGAGCUGCUUCUGCAAGGUGUUCAUGAUGAUGUUGACAUUAUAUUACUGCAAGAUUAAUGUGGUUUACAUAUCUUUAUGUACUGCCAUUUUUUGUUUCUGGUAAACUGGAAUAUAAAGUGAAAGAACAAACAUUUGAACAUACUUAAUGUAUUUUUAUAGAACUUUGUAAACGAAAGGAGAUUCAUGUUUUAGAAGUCUGUCCUUUUUUAUAUCUUGAAAGAAAAUCUAUGUAUGAUGCUAUAAAAUAAAUCCUAUUAUUUUUCUCAGGAAUCUGGUUAGGAAUUGCAGGCAAUGAGAUUUUUUGCGGGGCAGGGAUGGGAAUGUUUGUUCAUAAAUAAUUAGACAUUUUCUAUAGAUAUUUGACAUUCUGCGAAAGCAACAAGCAAACUGAAGACCAACUCCUAUGAGAAAUAUUAUGAUGUUUAUGUAAUAAAGACAUGUAACUGUCUUAAAUUU